GACGCGCCGAGCGGGACCCUGAGGAUCCAGCUGGCCGCAGGCUAUGGGCUGGGCGGCGGUUGAGACAGCGGCGAUAUUGGGAGGGGUAGGUGAGCGUCGCGAGGCAGCGUGAGCUUCUGAGUGAACGCGGUGCUUUUGGGAACGCGGGACGGGCGACCUGUGGCGCCAGGAGCGGGCCGAGGCGCGGCGGCGCGGCUGCCGUCUGGAUGGGAAGUUACGGUUUACAGCGAAGUCCACCCAGCGUUUCCGAGGUGAAGGCGCCGCGCCAGGCCGGGCGGGCGGCUGGUGAUGGGCAAGCCGGGUGUACCAAGUCCAGGAUGCACAUGAGGAGCGUUUGUAGCCGUCACUGAAUCACCUCAUGACUAGCGGGGCAGGCCUCUAAUUCACCGCAGGAUUUCCGAUCUCACUCUGUUGCCCAGGCUGGAGUGCAGUGGCACAAUCACAGCUGACCACAACCUUGACCUCCCAAGGCUCAGGUGAUCCUCCUGCCUCAGCCCCCAAGUAGCUGGGACCUACAGGCAAUCUGAAAGCAAAUCCUGUUUAGAUGCAGGCGAAGGUUCCUGGUGACCCAGGCUCUCACCUUACCGUCCCUUACCGUCCUCCUGAGGGUGUCCUGGAGCUUCAGUGCUGUGUGUUCUUGGCCUCCAUGCUGGGGGUGCCACCAAUUCCCACUGUCCAGGGCUUCCAGUGGACUCUCCGAGGUACUGAUGUAGAAACUUCCCCAUUCGGUGCACCAAGAGCAACCUCACACGGUGUGGGCCAAAUGAAGAGCUGCCAGAUCCCACAGCCCUUGAAGAUAAGGAUGGUCAAACAAAAUAAUAUCAUACCUGGAGAAACUCAGAUCUUGCUAAGAUUUACUGGUUGGGAAUCCAAAGUUAAUGCCAAGAAGCAGCCGCCAGUUGGGAUCAAAUGUGAGCCUAUGGAUCAAGGAAAUGAGCAAACAGGUGGCCAUGAAACAGAUGGUCAUAGAAUUGGUUCAGUGGUUGUGAGUGCAGCAACCCAAGAGUGUCUUAUCUGAAAUACCACCAGGAAUGUCUGGACACAGUAGACAAAGUUUUUUCAACUGGACGCCUUAGGAUACAUGCUUCCAAAAACAAAGUAGCCAAAAAGAAACCAGAGUCACAGAAUAUCAGAGCCAAAGGAACAUUUGGAGCAGGCCUAGCGUCUUGGCAGUCAUGGUGACAAUGACGUUGAAGGUGGGGGCUCCACCGAUGCUCUUCAUACAAAGAUCCGUGGUCAAUUCCCCAUCCUGCAGCAGUGAGUCCAGGACCACAGUAUAUUUCUGGCCCCCCCAGUGUCAGCCCAUUCAUGACAAAGCUUGACCAGUCUUUGCCAACCAGGACACCAACCUCAGCUGGCGUGAUGUUGAGGAAGGUUUUCCCUGGGACGGCGGCCCAGAUGGAAGACGGUUACCUGGCACGCUGGCCACAAUCUACCUCACUCUUAUCAGAGUCUGAGCUACUGGCAGUGCUUUCAGCUCUGAGUUGAGGCACCUCAAACCUUGUUUUUGUGGUGAAGGAUCCUAAAGUGCUGUGGGAGUGAUCACAUUUUUCACAACAGUAAGUCCCUGGCCCCACCUCUUCUGCCACAAACGUCAGCAUGGUGGUAUCAGCCGGCCCUUGGUCCAGCGAGAAGGCAGAGAUGAACAUUCUAGAAAUCAACGAGAAAUUGCGCCCCCAGUUGGCAGAGAACAAACAGCAGUUCGGAAACCUCAAAGAGAGAUGUUUUCUAACUCAACUGGCCGGCUUCCUGGCCAACCGACAGAAGAAAUACAAGUAUGAAGAGUGUAAAGACCUCAUAAAAUUUAUGCUGAGGAAUGAGCGACAGUUCAAGGAGGAGAAGCUUGCAGAGCAGCUGAAGCAAGCUGAGGAGCUCAGGCAAUAUAAAGUCCUGGUUCACUCUCAGGAACGAGAGCUGACGCAGUUAAAGGAGAAGUUACGGGAAGGGAGAGAUGCCUCCCGCUCAUUGAAUGAGCAUCUCCAGGCCCUCCUCACUCCGGAUGAGCCGGACAAGUCCCAGGGGCAGGACCUCCAAGAACAGCUGGCUGAGGGGUGUAGACUGGCACAGCACCUUGUCCAAAAGCUCAGCCCAGAAAAUGACGAAGAUGAGGAUGAAGAUGUUCAAGUUGAGGAGGAUGAGAAAGUACUGGAAUCAUCUGCCCCCAGGGAGGUGCAGAAGGCUGAAGAGAGCAAAGUCGCUGAGGACUCACUGGAGGAAUGUGCCAUCACUUGUUCAAAUAGCCACGGCCCUUGUGACUCCAACCAGCCUCACAAGAACAUCAAAAUCACAUUUGAGGAAGACGAAGUCAACUCAACUCUGGUUGUAGACAGAGAAUCCUCUCAUGAUGAAUGUCAGGAUGCUCUAAACAUUCUCCCAGUCCCUGGCCCCACCUCUUCUGCCACAAACGUCAGCAUGGUGGUAUCAGCCGGCCCUUUGUCCAGCGAGAAGGCAGAGAUGAACAUUCUAGAAAUCAAUGAGAAAUUGCGCCCCCAGCUGGCAGAGAAGAAACAGCAGUUCAGAAACCUCAAAGAGAAAUGUUUUCUAACUCAACUGGCCGGCUUCCUGGCCAACCAGCAGAACAAAUACAAGUAUGAAGAGUGUAAAGACCUCAUAAAAUUUAUGCUGAGGAAUGAGCGACAGUUCAAGGAGGAGAAGCUUGCAGAGCAGCUGAAGCAAGCUGAGGAGCUCAGGCAAUAUAAAGUCCUGGUUCACGCUCAGGAACGAGAGCUGACCCAGUUAAGGGAGAAGUUGCGGGAAGGGAGAGAUGCCUCCCGCUCAUUGAAUGAGCAUCUCCAGGCCCUCCUCACUCCGGAUGAGCCGGACAAGUCCCAGGGGCAGGACCUCCAAGAACAGCUGGCUGAGGGGUGUAGACUGGCACAGCACCUUGUCCAAAAGCUCAGCCCAGAAAAUGACAACGAUGACGAUGAAGAUGUUCAAAUUGAGGUGGCUGAGAAAGUGCAGAAAUCGUCUGCCCCCAGGGAGAUGCAGAAGGCUGAAGAAAAGGAAGUCCCUGAGGACUCACUGGAGGAAUGUGCCAUCACUUAUUCAAAUAGCCAUGGCCCUUAUGACUCCAACCAGCCACAUAGGAAAACCAAAAUCACAUUUGAGGAAGACAAAGUCGACUCAACUCUCAUUGGCUCAUCCUCUCAUGUUGAACGGGAAGAUGCUGUACACAUUAUUCCAGAAAAUGAAAGUGAUGAUGAGGAAGAGGAAGAAAAAGGGCCAGUGUCUCCCAGGAAUCUGCAGGAGUCUGAAGAGGAGGAAGUCCCCCAGGAGUCCUGGGAUGAAGGUUAUUCGACUCCCUCAAUUCCUCCUGAAAUGUUGGCCUCGUACAAGUCUUACAGCAGCACAUUUCACUCAUUAGAGGAACAGCAAGUCUGCAUGGCUGUUGACAUAGGCAGACAUCGGUGGGAUCAAGUGAAAAAGGAGGACCAAGAGGCAACAGGUCCCAGGCUCAGCAGGGAGCUGCUGGAUGAGAAAGGGCCUGAAGUCUUGCAGGACUCACUGGAUAGAUGUUAUUCAACUCCUUCAGGUUGUCUUGAACUGACUGACUCAUGCCAGCCCUACAGAAGUGCCUUUUACGUAUUGGAGCAACAGCGUGUUGGCUUGGCUGUUGACAUGGAUGAAAUUGAAAAGUACCAAGAAGUGGAAGAAGACCAAGACCCAUCAUGCCCCAGGCUCAGCAGGGAGCUGCUGGAUGAGAAAGAGCCUGAAGUCUUGCAGGACUCACUGGGUAGAUGGUAUUCGACUCCUUCAGGUUAUCUUGAACUGCCUGACUUAGGCCAGCCCUACAGCAGUGCUGUUUACUCAUUGGAGGAACAGUACCUUGGCUUGGCUCUUGACUUGGACAGAAUUAAAAAGGACCAAGAAGAGGAAGAAGACCAAGGCCCACCAUGCCCCAGGCUCAGCAGGGAGCUGCUGGAGGUAGUAGAGCCUGAAGUCUUGCAGGACUCACUGGAUAGAUGUUAUUCAACUCCUUCCAGUUGUCUUGAACAGCCUGACUCCUGCCAGCCCUAUGGAAGUUCCUUUUAUGCAUUGGAGGAAAAACAUGUUGGCUUUUCUCUUGACGUGGGAGAAAUUGAAAAGAAGGGGAAGGGGAAGAAAAGAAGGGGAAGAAGAUCAAAGAAGAAAAGAAGAAGGGGAAGAAAAGAAGGGGAAGAAAAUCAAAACCCACCAUGCCCCAGGCUCAGCAGGGAGCUGCUGGAUGAGAAAGAGCCUGAAGUCUUGCAGGACUCACUGGAUAGAUGUUAUUCGACUCCUUCAGGUUAUCUUGAACUGCCUGACUUAGGCCAGCCCUACAGCAGUGCUGUUUACUCAUUGGAGGAACAGUACCUUGGCUUGGCUCUUGACGUGGACAGAAUUAAAAAGGACCAAGAAGAGGAAGAAGACCAAGGCCCACCAUGCCCCAGGCUCAGCAGGGAGCUGCUGGAGGUAGUAGAGCCUGAAGUCUUGCAGGACUCACUGGAUAGAUGUUAUUCAACUCCUUCCAGUUGUCUUGAACAGCCUGACUCCUGCCAGCCCUAUGGAAGUUCCUUUUAUGCAUUGGAGGAAAAACAUGUUGGCUUUUCUCUUGACGUGGGAGAAAUUGAAAAGAAGGGGAAGGGGAAGAAAAGAAGGGGAAGAAGAUCAAAGAAGGAAAGAAGAAGGGGAAGAAAAGAAGGGGAAGAAGAUCAAAACCCACCAUGCCCCAGGCUCAACGGCGUGCUGAUGGAAGUGGAAGAGCCUGAAGUCUUGCAGGACUCACUGGAUGGAUGUUAUUCUACUCCGUCAAUGUACUUUGAACUACCUGACUCAUUCCAGCACUACAGAAGUGUGUUUUACUCAUUUGAGGAACAGCACAUCAGCUUCGCCCUUUACGUGGACAAUAGGUUUUUUACUUUGACGGUGACAAGUCUCCACCUGGUGUUCCAGAUGGAAGUCAUAUUCCCACAAUAAGCAGCCCUUACUAAGCCGAGAGAUGUCAUUCCUGCAGGCAGGACCUAUAGGCACGUGAAGUUUUGAAUGAAAGUACAGUUCCAUUUGGAAGCCCAGACAUAGGAUGGGUCAGUGGGCAUGGCUCUAUUCCUAUUCUCAAACCAUGCCAGUGGCAACCUGUGCUCAGUCUGAAGACAAUGGACCCACGUUAGGUGUGACACGUUCACAUAACUGUGCAGCACAUGCCGGGAGUGAUCAGUCAGACAUUUUAAUUUGAACCACGUAUCUCUGGGUAGCUACAAAAUUCCUCAGGGAUUUCAUUUUGCAGACAUGUCUCUGAGCUUCUAUACCUGCUCAAGGUCAUUGUCAUCUUUGUGUUUAGCUCAUCCAAAGGUGUUACCCUGGUUUCAAUGAACCUAACCUCAUUCUUCGUGUCUUCAGUGUUGGCUUGUUUUAGCUGAUCCAUCUGUAACACAGGAGGGAUCCUUGGCUGAGGAUUGUAUUUCAGAACCACCAACUGCUCUUGACAAUUGUUAACCCGCUAGGCUCCUUUGGUUAGAGAAGCCACAGUCCUUCAGCCUCCAAUUGGUGUCAGUACUUAGGAAGACCACAGCUAGAUGGACAAACAGCAUUGGGAGGCCUUAGCCCUGCUCCUCUCAAUUCCAUCCUGUAGAGAACAGGAGUCAGGAGCCGCUGGCAGGAGACAGCAUGUCACCCAGGACUCUGCCGGUGCAGAAUAUGAACAAUGCCAUGUUCUUGCAGAAAACGCUUAGCCUGAGUUUCAUAGGAGGUAAUCACCAGACAACUGCAGAAUGUAGAACACUGAGCAGGACAACUGACCUGUCUCCUUCACAUAGUCCUUAUCACCACAAAUCACACAACAAAAAGGAGAAGAGAUAUUUUGGGUUCAAAAAAAGUAAAAAGAUAAUGUAGCUGCAUUUCUUUAGUUAUUUUGAACCCCAAAUAUUUCCUCAUCUUUUUGUUGUUGUCAUGGAUGGUGGUGACAUGGACUUGUUUAUAGAGGACAGGUCAGCUGUCUGGCUCAAUGAUCUACAUUCUGAAGUUGUCUGAAAAUGUCUUCAUGAUUAAAUUCAGCCUAAACGUUUUGCCGGGAACACUGCAGAGACAAUGCUGUGAGUUUCCAACCUCAGCCCAUCUGCGGGCAGAGAAGGUCUAGUUUGUCCAUCACCAUUAUGAUAUCAGGACUGGUUACUUGGUUAAGGAGGGGUCUAGGAGAUCUGUCCCUUUUAGAGACACCUUACUUAUAAUGAAGUACUUGGGAAAGCGGUUUUCAAGAGUAUAAAUAUCCUGUAUUCUAAUGAUCAUCCUCUAAACAUUUUAUCAUUUAUUAAUCCUCCCUGCCUGUGUCUAUUAUUAUAUUCAUAUCUCUACGCUGGAAAUUUUGGGUCUCAAUUUUUACUGUGCCUUUGUUUUUACUAGUGUCUGCUGUUGCAAAAAGAAGAAAACAUUCUCUGCCUGAGUUUUAAUUUUUGUCCAAAGUUAAUUUUAAUCUAUACAAUUAAAACCUUUUGCCUAUCACUCUGGACUUUUGGAUUGUUUUUUACAUUCAGUGUUAUAAUAUUUGAUUAUGCUGAUUGGUUUUGGUGGGUACUGAUGCGAAUUAAUAAAAACAUUUCAUUUCCAUGUUUAUUUUCUAAUCUCUUCCACAUUGUAGGCUAUGUUUACCAUAUGUAGCAGAAUGUAUUUACAUUUCUUGGUUCUAGUCAUUUGUAUUCUUCGUGAGUGUGAGUGUGUGUGUGUCUGUGUGUGUGUGUCUGUGUGUGUGUCUGUGUGUGCCUUUGGCAUUUAGGAAGGGUUGUAUAGCUCAUGUUAAAUAUUGCACUAAAAAUGUUUUUGAUGGUUUUCCUCCCUUUGGACUAGACACACUUCUAAUAUUUGGUUUAUAGUUUUAAAUUAUAACUUUCAGCAUCAAAUAUUUCCAUACAACAGUCAAUUACAUGAUGUGUUUUCUUUUUCCUACCUCCUUUACCUGCCACUUCUCAUAAUAGUAUUUGAACCUAAACAUAUACCGGUGACAUUCUGUGAUUAUCAUCUUGCCCCUACCUUGGUUUUUGGUUUAGAUCCACAAUGAAAUAUAUUAACGCUCAUGAGCUAUUCAAAAGUGAAUGUCACAGUCGUCACUUGCUGAGUGGUACUCAUCCUUAACAGAGUCCUCAUGAGGGAAUCAGGUCUCGCUGAGUUUAGCAUGUUUAAUAAUCUUUUCUCACGGUCUCGAUACAUGGAUCGCAUUACUAGAUAUAAGGUGCUUGCCCAAAAUGAUUUUUCUGGAGUUUUUAGGAGAUAUUGUCUUCCUUGGGGGACAUACAUGGUGUAUGUUCUCAUUGUGGGAUUCUAUUUUGUUCUACCAGGACCUCUAAUUUCUGCCAGUUACUUCAUUCAUUUGUUCUCUUCACCAUGAGUCUCCAGAGGAUACUUCCAUGGUCCGUGCCUCCCCAUCUCCCAGCAAUUCUGCAUUUCCAAGAUUGGCACCUCUGGUCCUCUGCACGGUGAAGCCCCUUCCUUUCAAUUCCCCAGUAGCCAGUGCUCUAAUCCACCAGGUCUCAGGCAUGAUCUAUGUUUCUCCACACUCGCUUUCUGAGGAGAGUUUUGCCUGGGUUCUAUCAUGAACAGGCCCUCCCUGCUGUCCUGGCCUCUAUUUGCAUAGUGUUUCCUGCUCCCUCUGCCGUCGUGUGGCUCCCAGACCUGGCUAAAGAAAAUCACCUGAGGGCCACAGUGUUCCCUAGCCCUGGUGUUUAGGGCAGGAUUAUGGGUGAGAUUUUUGAGUCUCUAACUUGACCCCUACAGCUCUGAAGUGUAUGUUGAGAAAUUCAGCUGUUAUCAUCCUAGGUGGACUUGCUCCCUCCUAUCCUCCUACUUCAAAUGCAGAACUUCAAUCGUUUACAAAAGAAGACUGAAUCGUAUAAUAGAACACACCCUUAUUCAUUGGCUGGCUUCACCAAUCUCAUGGCUGAACUUGUAAAAAUACAAUCUUAGCCACAUACCUAUGAAAUGUAUAUGUGUGUGUAUAUAUAUACAUGAAUUUGCUUCUGAGAUUAUGGAGGCUGAAAUUCCCAAGAUGGAAGGAAAGCUGGAUACCCAGGAAAGCAUUUGUUUCCCAUUAGGCCUCUUAAUUCUCUCCUGGCCCUUGAUGGAUUGCAUGAGGCCCACCCCUAUUAAGGAGGGCAAUCUGCUUCACUUAGUCUGCCCAUCCCAAUGUUAAUCGUAUCUGAAAGACUCUCUGGAACACAACCAGAAUCAUGUUUGGCCAAAUGUCCUGGCACCCUGGUGCUCGGUCACAGUGACAAGUACAAGUAACUAUCACACAUGCCCUUUGUCAUAUUGGUGAUUUCCACUGUUUUUCUCCCAAACUGCAGCUUAUAUUUGUUCUCUUAGUACUGUUGAGCAAAAACUUUUAAUUUUCAUAAAGUCGAAUUUAUCAAUGUUUUCUUUAAUGGUUUGUGUUUAUUGAUAAUAAAGAACACUUUACCUAA